AAUCUACUAAAUAUUAAAAUACUGGAAGGAGCAAGAUAGCUUUGAUCCAGGGAGACCUUUUCCAUUUAUGUGCUUUAGUAAUCUGCCGCCAACAAGCUAUCUUCUUUAUGUUCUUCUACAACUGAUGUUGUUUUGUUUUCUCAUGUUUGUCUCUUAAUAGACAAAUGGAGGCAUGAGCUUCCUUAGAAUUACCCCUUCGACGCAUAGUUCUGUUUCAUCUGGACUUUUGAGGCUUAGUAUCUUUCUACUACUUAGCUUUCCUGACUCAAACGGAAAAGCCAUUUGGACAGCUCACCUGAAUAUAACAUUUCAGGUUGGAAAUGAGAUCACAUCGGAAUUAGGAGAGAGUGGAGUGUUCGGGAAUCAUUCUCCUCUGGAAAGGGUGUCUGGUGUGGUGGCACUUCCUGAAGGAUGGAAUCAGAAUGCCUGUCAUCCUUUGACCAAUUUCAGCAGGCCCAAACAGGCAGACUCAUGGCUGGCCCUCAUCGAACGUGGAGGCUGUACUUUUACACAUAAAAUCAACGUGGCAGCAGAGAAGGGAGCAAAUGGGGUGAUCAUCUACAACUAUCAAGGUACGGGCAGUAAAGUAUUUCCCAUGUCUCACCAGGGGACGGAAAAUAUAGUCGCGGUGAUGAUAAGCAACCUGAAAGGCAUGGAAAUUUUGCACUCGAUUCAGAAAGGAGUCUAUGUGACAGUCAUCAUUGAAGUGGGGAGAAUGCACAUGCAGUGGGUGAGCCAUUACAUCAUGUAUCUAUUUACCUUCCUGGCUGCCACAAUUGCCUACUUUUACUUAGAUUGCGUCUGGAGACUUACACCUAGAGUGCCCAAUUCUUUCACCAGGAGGCGAAGUCAAAUAAAGACAGAUGUGAAGAAAGCUAUUGACCAGCUUCAACUGCGAGUUCUCAAAGAAGGGGAUGAGGAAUUAGACCUAAAUGAAGACAACUGUGUUGUUUGCUUUGACACAUACAAACCCCAAGAUGUAGUACGCAUUUUAACUUGCAAACAUUUUUUCCAUAAGGCAUGCAUUGACCCCUGGCUUUUAGCCCAUAGGACAUGUCCCAUGUGCAAGUGUGACAUCCUGAAAACUUAAGAAAUCUGGAGAAUUUUCUGAAGAUGUAACCAGAUCUUUCCAAAUACAAAGAUUAGAUAAAUUGUCUUAUUGUACUUUAUGUAGAGAGAAAAUUUCAGCUUCUCUACCCAAGUAUGAACAAGGGUGAAAUUUGUGUUUUAAAAAUAAAACUCCUUAUCAUGCCCA